CAGCAUGUGUGCUGACCAGUGAACUAACAGGCAGUGCCUGCCAAUCUCUAGGUGGAUUUUUCCACUCAAGCUCUUCCACUUCCUCCACUGAGAAGCCAGAGGGUGCCAGAGACUAUGGGCUUCGGCAAGAACCAGGUGAGACCCCACAAGGAAGAAGACAAGAGCAGGAGUGCGUGAGCUGUGUGCCAAUGCCAGCUCUCUUGACAACUGCUAUAUUCUUAGGGAAACUGCCUGUUCCAAUCAAGAGUCUAAAUGACAAACAACAUGAUUAACACAUUUGCUGUAUGGUGUCGAGAGUAAAUGGAAACUUAAGGCUGAGAGGUGGGGAAAGAAUGAGCAUUCUAUGAUCCUAGAGCUGGCUGGGCCCAGGUGUUUCUGCAACAGCCGGCCAUGACUGAUCACAAGCUCUGGGCCAGGGGAGGUGAUGUGUUUUUCAUGGGGAACAUAAACCUUGGUCAGUUGGUGUCAUGGAGUCGGGGAGAGGAGCAGUUGCUGCAGCUGGUAGAUCCUUUCCGAUAGCACUAGUGAAGGGUGGUAACAUGUGGAAGAUCCUGAAUAGGAGCUAAUCAGAAGAUGACUUCUACUUGCCUCUGAGCCAUUUGACCAUAGUGCUACCUUAGCUGUCCUUCUCUGGCCCAGAACUUUUGAUUACUUGGGCCAAUUUGGAAUGUGGCUUUGUCUCCAGGGUCUUCUCUCCCUGCUCCAUUAUGUUGGAAUUUCCAGAGACUAUGGGCUUCAGCAAGAACCAGACUGGAGCCCUUCCCCGACUAUGUGACGUGCUACAAGUGCUGUGGGAAGAGCAAGACCAGUGCCUGCAGGAACUCUCCAGAGAGCAGACAGGAGACCUGGGCACGGAGCAGCCAGUGCCAGCUCAUUUCUAGCCCCUUCCAAGCCUGACCCCAGCGAUGACCUCUCAGAGGGCACGGGUUCCAGAAGUCUGUUGCAGGAAGCAGUUUCCCUGUGUGGCUGCCCUUGGAUCAACUUUGGGAGAAUUGGUGAGUUGUUAUGUGAAAUGAUGUCUUAAAAGACAGUACAGUCACAGCUCACACACAAAUAUAAAAUGAAUACCUGCCGAACAGCUUGUUUAAUUUGUGAGGGACUCAGUAAGAUCUUAUCACUGGUUCAUAGCAUUCAAAGUAACUGAUAUGGUUUGGCUAUGUCCCCACUCAAAUCUCAUCUUGAAUUGUAGCUCUCAGAAUUCCCAUGUGUCAUGGGAGGGACCUGGUGGAAGGUAAUAGAAUUGUGGGGGCAGGUUUCUCCCAUGCUGUUCUCGUGAUAGUGAAUAAGUCUCAUGAGAUCUGGUGGUUUCAUAAACGGGAGUUUCCCUGCAUGUGUCCUCCUGCCCACCGCCAUGUAAGAAGUCCCUUUGCUCUUUCUUCGUCUUCCACCAUGAUUGUGAGACCUCUCAGCUAUGUGAAACUGUGAGUCCGUUAAACCUCUUUCCUUCAUAAUUACCCAGUCUCAGGUAUGUCUUUAUCAGCAGCAUGAAAACAGACUAAUACAGUACCAUACCUAUAAGGCAGAAUGAUAACAUGAAUUUACAAAUAGAUGCAAAGCUGACUGAAUACACAGGGAGGGAAGUGAAAUUAAUUGUAUUUCAACUGGACAAUAAUUAUUGUGCCUAUGGACGAGAAUCAUUUGCAUUGCUACCAAUCAUCUAGAACUUACAGAGUUGCAGUGUAGCUCGAAGACAAUAAAAGACCUGACACCCCAUUGAAUCAGAUAAUCCAGAAGGCUGUGCUUAGACAAUGCCUAGUUUUGCAUUGAAAACACCUAGUAAUUUUUUUUAUUCAUCUUAAAAUCUUUCAGUUUUCAGAAGUGGGCCACGCAUCUGGCUCUGAGCUUCCUAGCAGCCAAAUCAAAGAGGAAACCAGCUUCAAAUGUAGUGUCUAUGUAUACUAGUCGUUCACAAUAAGUUCAGCUUCUCACUGCAUUGAGACCUGGUUCUCCUUCCAGAGGGGCCUCAUCAAGGGAACUCAAGUGAUGUAGAAAGCAACAUCCUCAAUAAUAUUCUUGCAGCAAAUACAGUGGUGACACUUGUGGAGCUGUGUCCAUAGGCCAGGGCAGUGGCUCUGAGUGUGGUCCCAGGACAAACAGCAUCAGCAUCACUUGGGAACUUGUUAGAAAUGCAGAUACUCAGGCCCCACCCCAGACUUACUGAGCAAUCUGUGUUUUAAUAAUCCCUCUGGGUGACUCUGAUGCAAGCUGAAGUUUGAGAAUCAUGGGACAAGAGUUCUCAACCCUGCAGUCAAACGUUAGAAUUACCUGUAAGGCUUUCAAAGGACAUGAUGCCUGGGCCCACCCAAACCAAUUCAUGCAGGAUCCCUGUGUGCCACGCCGGCUAGGUCUAUUUCUAAAGCUCCCCAGGUAGUCGUACCAUGAAGCUAGAAGGGAGACCCAUUGCUGCUUAGUUGUUUAAUGCAAACUGAUUGGCCAACAGAUGUGCCAUCUGCUCCAGAGAAAUCCAGACCUUUACUUGCAAAGCUUAUAGGAGAGGGCGCCUUCCUUCUUUCCUUCUUCCCUUCCUCCCUCCCUUUCUUACUUCCUUCUAUCUUCAACACUGAGCACUACCGUGUACAUGGCAGAGUCCAAGGGUGCAUUAGACAGGAUAGGUUCCUGAUCCUGAGGAGUCAGCACCUAAUGAGAGCUUUGAAAGUAGUCUAGUGGGAAUUCCAGGCAGGCAAGGGUGUCGGUGAUGUGGACAGGAUGGUAGGGCAGCCCUCGGUCCAUCCCCCAUCCUUGUCUGAUGCUGCUUUUCUUGGCAGGUUGUGAGGGGAUGUGGGACAACAUAAGCUGCUGGCCCUCUUCUGUGCCGGGCCGGAUGGUGGAGGUGGAAUGCCCGAGAUUCCUCCGGAUGCUCACCAGCAGAAAUGGUUCCUUGUUCCGAAACUGCACACAGGAUGGCUGGUCAGAAACCUUCCCCAGGCCUAAUCUGGCCUGUGGCGUUAAUGUGAACGACUCUUCCAACGAGAAGCGGCACUCCUACCUGCUGAAGCUGAAAGUCAUGUACACCGUGGGCUACAGCUCCUCCCUGGUCAUGCUCCUGGUCGCCCUUGGCAUCCUCUGUGCUUUCCGGAGGCUCCACUGCACUCGCAACUACAUCCACAUGCACCUGUUCGUGUCCUUCAUCCUUCGUGCCCUGUCCAACUUCAUCAAGGACGCCGUGCUCUUCUCCUCAGAUGAUGUCACCUACUGCGAUGCCCACAGGGCGGGCUGCAAGCUGGUCAUGGUGCUGUUCCAGUACUGCAUCAUGGCCAACUACUCCUGGCUGCUGGUGGAAGGCCUCUACCUUCACACACUCCUCGCCAUCUCCUUCUUCUCUGAAAGAAAGUACCUCCAGGGAUUUGUGGCAUUCGGAUGGGGUUCUCCAGCCAUUUUUGUUGCUUUGUGGGCUAUUGCCAGACACUUUCUGGAAGAUGUUGGCUGUCCCUCCCUUAGGUGCUGGGACAUCAAUGCCAACGCAUCCAUCUGGUGGAUCAUUCGUGGUCCUGUGAUCCUCUCCAUCCUGAUUAAUUUCAUCCUUUUCAUAAACAUUCUAAGAAUCCUGAUGAGAAAACUUAGAACCCAAGAAACAAGAGGAAAUGAAGUCAGCCAUUAUAAGCGCCUGGCCAGGUCCACUCUCCUGCUGAUCCCCCUCUUUGGCAUCCACUACAUCGUCUUCGCCUUCUCCCCAGAGGACGCUAUGGAGAUCCAGCUGUUUUUUGAACUAGCCCUUGGCUCAUUCCAGGGACUGGUGGUGGCCGUCCUCUACUGCUUCCUCAAUGGGGAGGUGAGUAGUCUUGGGUCACCCAGGUACCCAGGAGAGCUCCUAGCCAUUGGUUUCCGGGUCAGAAGGAGCUACCUGGGAGGGGUGGUAGGAAGGGGGAUGGAAAGGGUCAGAGGGAGUCCUGGGUCUGGUGGCAGGUGGCUUGGCCAGUUCUUUUAGGAGUCUGAAUUUGCUUAAUGGGAGCAAGGCUUGUUCAAACCAUGGCUGGACCCUGUUCCUAGUUUCUCAUUCCACAGAAAUAAAUUCUGUAGGUCUGGACUGGGGUCUGAGAAAGUGUUUUUUAACAAGCA